AGAGUCGAGAGUGGGAGAAGAGCGGAGCGUGUGAGCAGUACUGCGGCCUCCUCUCCUCUCCUAACCUCGCUCUCGCGGCCUAGCUUUACCCGCCCGCCUGCUCGGCGACCAGCGGGGAUCCUCCCCCAGCCGCAAGUCCACGAAGAAAGCAACGAAUGAAAAUUAUGAAGACAACGAGAAGUCAGACUCCUCCGGGUCGCGCUCCAGCUGCUUCGGCUUCGUCGCCUACUCUGUGAACUCCGGGGAGAGAUCUCGAGUCAAGAUUAAGACCUUAACCCACCAACCUGCCUGUUCGGACACCCCCCGGGCCGGCCGCUGUCUGUCCCCUUCUCCAUCGCCCUCUCCCAGAAAGCUCCGGUGCUUGGACCAGCUAGAGUCUGAGAAAGAGGAGAGGCGCGAACGCCACUCCAAAAAGAGAAGGGUUAAAGAGGGCAACCCUAACGAUACGCUUGACUUUCUGUGGCUGGGAACACCUUCCACCAUGACCACCUCAGCAAGUUCCCACUUAAAUAAAGGCAUCAAGCAGGUGUACAUGUCCCUGCCUCAGGGUGAGAAAGUCCAGGCCAUGUAUAUCUGGAUCGAUGGUACUGGAGAAGGACUGCGCUGCAAGACCCGGACCCUGGACAGUGAGCCCAAGUGUGUGGAAGAGUUGCCUGAGUGGAAUUUCGAUGGCUCUAGUACUUUACAGUCUGAGGGUUCCAACAGUGACAUGUAUCUCGUGCCUGCUGCCAUGUUUCGGGACCCCUUCCGUAAGGACCCUAACAAGCUGGUGUUAUGUGAAGUUUUCAAGUACAAUCGAAGGCCUGCAGAGACCAAUUUGAGGCACACCUGUAAACGGAUAAUGGACAUGGUGAGCAACCAGCACCCCUGGUUUGGCAUGGAGCAGGAGUAUACCCUCAUGGGGACAGAUGGGCACCCCUUUGGUUGGCCUUCCAACGGCUUCCCAGGGCCCCAGGGUCCAUAUUACUGUGGUGUGGGAGCAGACAGAGCCUAUGGCAGGGACAUCGUGGAGGCCCAUUACCGGGCCUGCUUGUAUGCUGGAGUCAAGAUUGCGGGGACUAAUGCCGAGGUCAUGCCUGCCCAGUGGGAAUUUCAGAUUGGACCUUGUGAAGGAAUCAGCAUGGGAGAUCAUCUCUGGGUGGCCCGUUUCAUCUUGCAUCGUGUGUGUGAAGACUUUGGAGUGAUAGCAACCUUUGAUCCUAAGCCCAUUCCUGGGAACUGGAAUGGUGCAGGCUGCCAUACCAACUUCAGCACCAAGGCCAUGCGGGAGGAGAAUGGUCUGAAGUACAUCGAGGAGGCCAUUGAGAAACUAAGCAAGCGGCACCAGUACCACAUCCGUGCCUAUGAUCCCAAGGGAGGCCUGGACAAUGCCCGACGUCUAACUGGAUUCCAUGAAACCUCCAACAUCAACGACUUUUCUGCUGGUGUAGCCAAUCGUAGCGCCAGCAUACGCAUUCCCCGGACUGUUGGCCAGGAGAAGAAGGGUUACUUUGAAGAUCGUCGCCCCUCUGCCAACUGCGACCCCUUUUCGGUGACAGAAGCCCUCAUCCGCACGUGUCUUCUCAAUGAAACCGGCGAUGAGCCCUUCCAGUACAAAAAUUAAGUGGACUAGACCUCCAGCUGUUGAGCCCCUCCUAGUUCUUCAUCCCACUCCAACUCUUCCCCCUCUCCCAGUUGUCCCGAUUGUAACUCAAAGGGUGGAAUAUCAAGGUCGUUUUUUUCAUUCCAUGUGCCCAGUUAAUCUUGCUUUCUUUGUUUGGCUGGGAUAGAGGGGUCAAGUUAUUAAUUUCUUCACACCUACCCUCCUUUUUUUCCCUAUCACUGAAGCUUUUUAGUGCAUUAGUGGGGAGGAGGGUGGGGAGACAUAACCACUGCUUCCAUUUAAUGGGGUGCACCUGUCCAAUAGGCGUAGCUAUCCGGACAGAGCACGUUUGCAGAAGGGGGUCUCUUCUUCCAGGUAGCUGAAAGGGGAAGACCUGACGUACUCUGGUUAGGUUAGGACUUGCCCUCGUGGUGGAAACUUUUCUUAAAAAGUUAUAACCAACUUUUCUAUUAAAAGUGGGAAUUAGGAGAGAAGGUAGGGGUUGGGAAUCAGAGAGAAUGGCUUUGGUCUCUUGCUUGUGGGACUAGCCUGGCUUGGGACUAAAUGCCCUGCUCUGAACACGAAGCUUAGUAUAAACUGAUGGAUAUCCCUACCUUGAAAGAAGAAAAGGUUCUUACUGCUUGGUCCUUGAUUUAUCACACAAAGCAGAAUAGUAUUUUUAUAUUUAAAUGUAAAGACAAAAAACUAUAUGUAUGGUUUUGUGGAUUAUGUGUGUUUUGCUAAAGGAAAAAACCAUCCAGGUCACGGGGCACCAAAUUUGAGACAAAUAGUCGGAUUAGAAAUAAAGCAUCUCAUUUUGAGUAGAGAGCAAGGGAAGUGGUUCUUAGAUGGUGAUCUGGGAUUAGGCCCUCAAGACCCUUUUGGGUUUCUGCCCUGCCCACCCUCUGGAGAAGGUGGGCACUGGAUUAGUUAACAGACAACACGUUACUAGCAGUCACUUGAUCUCCGUGGCUUUGGUUUAAAAGACACACUUGUCCACAUAGGUUUAGAGAUAAGAGUUGGCUGGUCAACUUGAGCAUGUUACUGACAGAGGGGGUAUUGGGGUUAUUUUCUGGUAGGAAUAGCAUGUCACUAAAGCAGGCCUUUUGAUAUUAAAUUUUUUAAAAAGCAAAAUUAUAGAAGUUUAGAUUUUAAUCAAAUUUGUAGGGUUUCUAGGUAAUUUUUACAGAAUUGCUUGUUUGCUUCAACUGUCUCCUACCUCUGCUCUUGGAGGAGAUGGGGACAGGGCUGGAGUCAAAACACUUGUAAUUUUGUAUCUUGAUGUCUUUGUUAAGACUGCUGAAGAAUUAUUUUUUUUCUUUUAUAAUAAGGAAUAAACCCCACCUUUAUUCCUUCAUUUCAUCUACCAUUUUCUGGUUCUUGUGUUGGCUGUGGCAGGCCAGCUGUGGUUUUCUUUUGCCAUGACAACUUCUAAUUGCCAUGUACAGUAUGUUCAAAGUCAAAUAACUCCUCAUUGUAAACAAACUGUGUAACUGCCCAAAGCAGCACUUAUAAAUCAGCCUAACAUAAGAUCUCUCUGAUGUGUUUGUGAUUCUUUCAAAUCCCUAUGUGCCAUUAUAUUUCUUUAUUUCCUAAAACAGGCAAAAUAAGCUCAAGUUUAUGUACUCUGAGUUUUUAAAACACUGGAGUGAUGUUGCUGACCAGCCGUUUCCUGUACCUCUCUAAGUUGGGUAUUUGGGACUUAAGGGAUUAAGUUUUUCACCUAGACUUAGUUACACACAAUCUUGGCAUUUCCUAGCCUAGAGGUUUGUAGCAGGGUACAAGCCCCACUCCUCCCCCUUCCUUUGCUCCCCUGAGUUUGGUUUUGGCUUACCAUAACAUUGUUUUGACCAUUCCUAGCCUAAUACAAUAGCCUAACAUAAUGUAAGAUUAACUGGCUUUACGAUUUCUAUUCUCUGCUCUCAGUGAUAAGAAACAAAUAUUAGCUACCCUGCUACCCUGGUUGAAGCCUUCCAAGGCUGGCUAUGCCCUAGGCAUGGGCUCAUCCUUGGGUGUAUCUUGCCUUGCAGGAAGACCAGUGGACCGAUUGUGAUUCUCAAAAGCUCUGUGUUGUCACCUGUGCCCUUGCCCCUUGCUCUUAUCUUGGUCCGUGUAUCUGGGAGUUCUUCCACCUUAUCUUGGCCAAUUCCUACCUUCGUUCAUUCCUCAUGAGGUUGGGUAAAAGCUCCCUCCGGCUCCCAUGAUGCUGUGCAUAUACCUAGCAAAAAGCAAUUAUUGGACACAUUGGAGUGCAAUAUUAUUAAUAGCAUUAAUACUACUAAUAAUGUGGGCAAUAGUGAUUGUUUUUAAAAGGCAGUAUACUCUUACCAGUGCGAGGUAGCUGGGGCCUGUGAUAGUUUUUAGAGAUAAGUUCUUCAGGCAACUGUGUAUUUUACACUAGUCAAGUAAUCCUAGAUAUCCGUGGUUUUUCUUAAGAAAGUUGGCUCGUAAUAUGAUUUAAUAUUCAAAGUAGAGUCAUCUACCUAUUAGCUUGCUGGCGUGGUCCUAGUUUAUGCCUGUUUCAGCAUGAUUGUUGAGUACCCUGUUUCAUCCUUAGCAUUUUCUUGAUUUUGUUGUUAAAUGAUGUAUACCCUUAUUUCCAUUGAAUCUGUGCUUCCACCCCCCCAACUGAAGUUGUCUUCCCUUUGCUUGGCCACCCUUACAGCCUCUUGGAUGGUGUAUCCUACAGUGUAAGCACUAAACUGAAGAGGCAGUGACCUGAGCACUUUGGAUUUUGUUCAUUGUAAUCAAUUCCAUGACAAAAUGAUUGCAUGAGAAGGAAUUUUAAAUUCAUAGGAUCAGAAUUUAGGUGAAAACAACCAGCAUAUUUGUUUCUUCACCCUCUCACCUAGAAUUAGCUUUGACCUACAGGUCACAGUGCAAUCCCCUUGUAUUUCUAAGGUGUUUUUUAUAGUUCAUUUGCAGACAAUGGGUUAUGUGAUAACUUUUAUCAGUGAUAGAUUAAACAGAAUAAUGACCAAGCUUUCAACCUUAAGGAGUCAGGCCAGUAUUUACAAAAGGAGGUCUCCAUGAACUCCUUAAAUAUGAGUUCCCCUAAUAUCAUCUUGCCAGGUACUAAAUAACAACUGAUAGCACAAGCUAUAGGGAAUUUGAAAGAAUUCCAUGGAUGGGUGUUGUCUAGGGCCUUUUGUUGUUUUUGAGACGGGGUCUGACUCUCACCCAGGCUGGAGUAUAGUGUGGCGCAAUCUUGGCUCACUGCAACUUCUGCCUCCCAGAUUCAAGCGAUUCUCCUGCCUCAGCCUCCCAAGUAGCUGAGACUACAGGUGUGCACCACCAUGCUCAGCUAAUUUUUGUAUUUUUAGUACAGAUGGGGUUUCACCAUGUUGGCCAGGCUGGUCUUGAACUCCUGAUCUCCCAAAGUGAGGUCUUGAACUGGUCUUGAACUCCUCCACCUCCCAAAGUGCUGGGAUUACAGGCGUGAGCCACUGCACCCGGCCUAGGGCCAUGUAAAAAGCCAGAUCUGUGCUGCUGUCUGUGUAGAAGGGUAGACAAGUGGAUGAGAAGUUCCUGAACUAUUCUUGGCCCUUUUACCACUAAGUGAAAGUAACUUGCUGCCCCAAAGAAAGAUGUCUCAUCAUUCGACAGGACUUUCUAGUUGAACUUCAUGAAAGCAAGAGAUCCUGUUUUUCUUGCUCACCACUGUAUCUUGAGACCUGUUGUAGUGCCUGCAAUACUUAUUUAAUAAGUUAUUUUUAAGUAUCAGUUUUGUGAGCUUUAACUCUAUGAGGUCUUUGUUGUUUGACUGUAUUUUAACUCUGGCCAUGACAGCAAGACAAAGUUCCAUUUUUAUUGAGCUUAAAAAGAAUCAAGGCCAGGUGAAGUGGCUUACGCCUGUGAUCCCAACACUUUGUGAGGCUGCAGCAGGAGGAUCUCUUGAGCCCAGGAGUUUGAGACCGUUCUAGGCAAUGUAGUGAGGUCCAGACUCCACAAAAUAAUUUUUUUUUAAAUUGCACGCCUGUAGUCUCAGCUAUCAGGAGGCUGAGAUGGGAGGAUGACUUGAGCCCAGGAAAUUGAAGCUGCAGUGAAUUGUGAUUGCACCACUGCACUCCAGCCUGGGUGACAGAUCAAGACCUUGCCUAAACAAAACAAAACAAACAAAACCCCAAAAAACAAAUUGAAAAUGUUGAUUCUUUUUACUACAAACAUUAUGGCAGCACUAAAAACUUCGUGGGAGUGUACUGUGGAAAAUAGUGUACUUAAUUAAUUCUCAUUGUAAUCAGGCUACCAAGAGCCUUGUGUUGCUUUAAGAGUUAUAACUGCCAGGCACAGUGGCUCAUGCCUAUAAUCCCAGCACCUUGAGAGGCCGAGGCAGGUGGAUCACCUGAGAUCGGGAGUUUGAGACCAGCCGGGCCAAUAUGGUGAAACAAGCUGUGUCUCUACUAAAUACAAAAAAUUAGCCGGGCGUGGUGGCACAUGCCUGUAAUCCCAGCUGCUUGGGAGACUGAGACAGGAGAAUUGCUUGAACCUGGAAGGCGGAGGUUGCAGUGAGCUGAGAUUGCAACAUUGUACUCCAGCCUGGGCAACAAGAGGGAAACUCCAUCUCAAAAAAAAAAAAAAAGUUGUAACUGAGGCUGGGCAUGGUGGCUCAUACCUGUAAUCCCAGCACUUUGAAAAGCCGAGGCAGGUAGAUCACUUGAGCUCAGAAGUUCGAGACUAGCCUGGGCAACAUGACAAAACCCCAUCUCUACAAAAAAUACGAAAAAUUAGCUGGGCGUGGUGGCAUGCACCUGUAGUCCUAGCUACCUGGGAGGCUGAGGUGGGAAGAUUACUUGAAGCUGCAGUGAGCCAUGGUUGUGCCACUGCCCUCCAGUCUGGGCAACAAAGUGAGACCCUGUCUCAAAAAAACAAAAAAAAAUUAUAACUGAUGUAAACUGGCAGUUUAGGCUGGGUGUGGUGGCUCAAGCCUGUAAUCCUAGCACUUUGGGAGGCCAAGGCAGGUGGAUCACCUGAGUUCAGGAGUUCGAGACCAGCGUGGCCAACAUGGUGAAACCUUGUCUCUAUUAAAAAUACCAAAAUUAGCAAGAUGUGGUGGUGGGUGCCUAUAAUUCCAGCUACUCAGGAGGCUGAGGCAGGAGGAUCGCUGGAGCCAGGGAGGCAGAGGUUACAGUAAGCAAAGAUCACUCCACUUCACUCCAGCCUGGGCAAAAGAGUGAGACAUAUCAAAAAAUAAACAAAUAAAUAAAUAAAUAAGUGGCAGUUCAUCAUUUAACUCCAAAGACUUUGCGUACAUUUCUACUGAAAACAAUCUGAGCUGAUUAGAACCCUGCCAUUUUAUAGCCUUUAGCUCGAUCUCCGACCGUUCAUUUAAAAAAAUUCUACUUCAGGCCGGGCAUGGUGGCUCAAGCCUGUAAUCCCAUCACUGUAGGAGGCCAAAGUGGGCAGAUCACUUAAGGUCAGGAGUUUGAGACCAGCCUGGCCACCAUGGUGAAACCCCAUCUCUACUAAAAAUACAAAAAUUAGCCGGGCUUGGUGGUGAGCACCUGUAAUCCCACCCUGCCGAGUGGCAGGCUGAGGCAGGAGAAUCGCUUGAGCCCAAGAGCCGGAGGUUGCAGUGAGCCAAGCUUGCACCAUUGCACUCCAGCCUAGGCAACAGAGUGUGACUCCAUCUCAAGAAAAAAAAAAUUCUAUUUCAUUUUACAAUAUGCAGAUAUAUGUCCAUACACAUGCAUAAUAUAAAUGUAUACCAUAUUUGUGAGAAUAUGCAUAUAUGUACACAUUAGAUACACAAUACAAGCACAAUACAUAUGUCUUUUGCCCAAGAUACAGCAUUUUGUAAAGGAGACAGGAAUUUAGUAAUAUAUGUUCCAGAAACAGUACACAAGAGAAUUCGCCGAGAUGAGAAAGUUGUCACUAGGAAUGGGGAGUGGUAAGAUGUAGAAGGUAUAAUUGUUCUUAAAGUUCUACUGCCAACUCUUUCCAAUUAAUUACCCACUCUGCCAUGCUUUAUGGACAGGAGGUUGUCGGACACUGUCAAUUAAUAAAUAUUUGAGCAUGAUACACUGCUUGGAGCUCCUCUAAUAUAGGAGAGUGAUAUCCUAGUGCAUGUUACAGAGGGAGUGUCCACACAGUUCCUAUUGUCAUUUGAUGAGUUACUUUUCAGGGGCCUUGUACCUGAGCAAGUUGUCCUCUUUUUGAUGGAUUUCAGAUUGAGUUACCUGCAUUGUCUUGAGAUUGCAGCGUGUUUCCUCCACUGUACGGCGUAGUCAGCAGAUCUAUUAGUUAAACUCCAGUGGGCCCUCAGUCACUAAAUCUAUCCUCUGUGUUGAAGGCUUUCUGCAUUUGCCUUUCAAUAAAGGUUUAGAAUAAC